CCCCUCCCCUCCCGGCUCCGCUUGGCUCCGGGCAGGUAGAGCCGGGCUCCGGGCGCGCGCGGGGCCGCAGCAGCUGCUCCCGAUCUCGCCUCGGCCCAGCGCAGGGCCUCGCACGCCCAUGGCCGGCUCGGAGCAGCAGCGGCCGCGGCGGCGGGACGACGGAGACUCGGACGCGGCAGCGGCGGCGGCGGCGCCCCUGCAGGACGCGGAGCUGGCCCUGGCCGGCAUCAACAUGCUGCUCAACAACGGCUUCAGGGAGUCGGACCAGCUUUUCAAACAAUACAGAUACGCACAAUUGCUUUGCCGUGCAGGAAUUUAAAAAUUUCAGCUCAACUCUGCCCACUCAUCUCUCUGCCUUGUCUUCUGCAAACUCAGUCCUCAAAAUGAGUUCCUGAUGUCUUUCAAGCAGGCGUUAUUUAUUAAGAAUUUUUCCAACGUAAAUAAAGGAAGGAAGAAAAUGGAGGGAUUUUUAAAAAGUAUGAGAAUGUAGGCGAAAAUACUACCUUUACAUUGAAAGCAUGAAAUUUUUGCACUAUCUAAGAAAUUUUAUGCACUGUUAAUAGAAGGCAGUAUAUGAGUGGUUGGAAAACUCUCUCCCAGCAACAGCAGAGAGAUGCCCCUUCAAAGAUACUUCUCUGUGGAAAAAGUUUUUUGACUUCUGAGAAAACCUCAGCGCUUCCUGGAGAAACUCAAAGGCGCUUGUAAGAGAUGUUGAGUCAGCAGGCCUCUGAGCCUCUUCUCUGCCUAAAACCAUGUCAGAUUCUUGGGAGGACUGGAAGGACUUGCAGGCUGUCCAUGAUUUCUAGACAAGUCAUCUGCUCACAGACAAGAAUGUGUCUCUGCCUUGCUCCUGGAGACGAUAGGAGAGUCCACAGAUGCAGAGAUAACUUCUACAGUAAAAGGAUUCACAUGUGUCCUGUCAAAGCCAUUUUGGGGCAAGUUCCUUCAGUAAUAUGCAGAUUGCACUCUGACACCCAGAAGCUAUCCAUCAAACCCCCAGAGAGAUCUGUCUUCAGGGGAGAUGUCACCCCAAGCUUUAGACGCUCUGUGGCUCCCAGUCUUGUGUAGGAUAAAGCCCAGCCUCCUGGCCUGGCCUCCGAUGUCCUGUGAUGUGGCCCUGUCUGCUUCCUGUCCUGCUGCCCUUGUCCCUUCCAUGCUAGUUGUGCUGGAAUAUUUUACGUCAUCCAGCCAGAAAUCAUAGCCCACUAAUGAGUUUUGGAGCCAGCUUUGUCAGUUUUUUGAAUGCCAUGAUGACAUUUGAGGAAGAAAAAAUGCAGUUGGCAUGUGAUGACUUAAAAACCACAGAAAAACUGUGUGAAAGUGAAGAGGCUGGAGUAAUUGAAACAAUCAAGAAUAAAAUUAAGAAGAACGUUGAUGUCCGAAAAUCCGCCCCCUCUAUGGUUGAUCGGCUUCAGAGGCAGAUAAUCAUAGCUGACUGCCAGGUUUACCUGGCUGUGCUUUCAUUUGUAAAACAAGAAUUGUCAGCUUAUAUCAAAGGUGGGUGGAUCCUUAGGAAAGCCUGGAAGAUUUACAAUAAAUGCUAUCUGGACAUCAAUGCCCUUCAGGAGCUGUAUCAGAAGAAGCUAACUGAAGAGUCCUUGACUUCUGAUGCUGCAAAUGAUAAUCACAUUGUGGCUGAAGGGGUGUCUGAGGAGUCUCUGAACAGACUGAAAGGUGCUGUUAGCUUUGGAUAUGGCCUUUUUCACCUUUGCAUAUCCAUGGUGCCCCCAAACCUGCUCAAAAUCAUCAACCUGCUGGGUUUUCCUGGAGACCGCCUACAGGGGCUUUCUUCACUGAUGUAUGCAAGCGAAAGUAAGGACAUGAAGGCCCCUUUAGCUACAUUAGCUCUGCUCUGGUAUCAUACUGUAGUCCGCCCGUUUUUUGCCUUGGAUGGCAGUGAUAACAAGGCAGGCCUGGAUGAAGCUAAGGAAAUUCUCCUUAAAAAAGAAGCUGCUUAUCCAAAUUCUUCCCUCUUUAUGUUUUUCAAGGGACGGAUACAACGACUAGAGUGUCAAAUCAACAGUGCCUUGACAUCUUUCCACACUGCUUUGGAACUUGCAGUAGACCAGAGAGAAAUUCAACAUGUCUGUCUGUAUGAAAUUGGUUGGUGCAGCAUGAUAGAGCUCAAUUUCAAGGAUGCAUUUGAUUCCUUUGAGAGGCUAAAAAAUGAGUCCAGGUGGUCCCAGUGCUAUUAUGCCUACUUGACUGCAGUUUGUCAGGGAGCCACUGGUGAUGUGGAUGGGGCACAGAUUGUCUUUAAAGAAGUUCAGAAACUCUUCAAAAGGAAAAACAAUCAGAUUGAACAGUUCUCGGUGAAAAAGGCAGAGCGAUUUCGGAAGCAAACCCCAACCAAAGCGCUCUGUGUGUUGGCGUCUAUUGAAGUGUUGUACUUGUGGAAAGCUCUUCCAAACUGUUCCUUCCCCAACCUGCAGAGGAUGAGUCAAGCUUGCCAUGAAGUGGAUGACUCAUCUGUUGUUGGAUUAAAGUAUUUGCUUCUUGGUGCCAUACACAAAUGUCUAGGAAACUCAGAAGAUGCUGUUCAGUACUUCCAGCGAGCUGUUAAAGAUGAAUUGUGUCGUCAGAAUAACUUAUAUGUUCAGCCGUAUGCCUGUUAUGAACUUGGCUGUCUUCUAUUAGACAAACCAGAGACUGUAGGAAGAGGCAGAGCUCUACUUCUUCAAGCAAAGGAGGAUUUCUCUGGCUACGACUUUGAAAACAGAUUGCAUGUCCGCAUCCAUGCUGCUCUGGCCUCUCUGAGGGAAUUGGUUCCUCAGUGACAGACCCGGAACACCCGCUCCGUCCCUCCCCACCCAGGGUCCGCACUUUAAAAUAAAAGCAGAGGACAAAGCUCUUGUGAAGAUGGGCUUUUCUUCUGAAAACCACCUGUGCCAGGGACACAUUUUCCCAGUUAAGCUGACAUAUUAAAGAUCUCCUCUUUUAAACAUGUAGCUGAAAAGUAAUAAUGAUGUUGAGGAGGAUGAUGAUGGUAAUAAUAACUAACCACCUGGGGAGAGGGUUAAGUGACCUUGCUCAAACGUUUUAGUUUUGUGAUUUAUUAUUUUUAAAAUAAAAUCAAACGGAACAUCCAACCCAAGAUCCUGUAGGAACACCUACCUUAAGCACAUAUCUGAAUGGGUAACAUGAUGAGGUACCUGUAAAAUUAUUAACAAUAUCAUGACAUAGCAUUUAUAUUUGUGUUUUGAAAAAAUAAAAGUGCUUUCUAGUGUUUUACUUUAUCCUCAAAAUACUCCAGUGAAUAACAUAGCACAGAUAUUCUUAACCCCACUUUGCAGACAGUGAAACUCAGGCACAAAAAGGCAAAUUGACUUAUCCCAAUUAAUUAUUCCUGUUAUCAGCAGAGCAAUGAAUAGAAAGCAGAUCUCCUGACCACCAACUGACUUUUAUUGUAAAAAUAAUUCAUGUUAAUAGGCCAGAAUUCCAUGUUUUACUUAUUAAAAGAACAAAAUCUUCAGCUGAAGUUAUGUCACCAGAAAUAGUCAUCUCCAGAUUGUCUACAGAAUGUUUCAAAGCGAUGGACACUCUUUUUCCUUUGAAAGCCAACCAAGUAAGAGCAAAUAUUAAUAGAAGAUAAUUUUACAACUAAAAGUGUGACUCUUUUGCUAAUCUAUUAGCCUAGUCUAUAGAUUAGACAAACAGUAUCUACAUUUUAGGAGUUUACCUUUCUUUGUGAAAAUUGUCAAAUUACCAACUUUUGGAAAUCUUUUGACACAUUACUUGAAAAGGUUAUUCGUGAAUGAACAUAGAUUUUGGCCUCAAAAUAUUUGCUGGUGGAACAUUUGCUGGGCUACACAGUGCCAGGAUUUAAUCAUUUUCCCCUUAGCUCAGGUUAUUUAGAUAUUAUACAAGGAAUUCAAAGUUAUUUUUUUAUUCUUCAUUGCUAAUUUUUGUCAUUUAAUUUACCUCCAUGCCCGGUACUGCAAACCUGUGGUUUUGAAGAAUCUAAAUACCUCAGUCACUUUUAAGAAUCUCUGCCAUAAUUUGGCUCAAUGUUUAAGGUUAGAUUUUUAAAGAAAUUUUUAUUGAGCUAAAGGAUAUCAUUUUAGGGUAUCGUUUAUUUACAAAUUCUUUUGGCUGAAACAUGAUCUCAUAUUAAUAUUUUAAUAUUUCUUUUCAAAAUAAAACAGAAAAGCAAGUAGAAUGUUGGCAAAUUUUAUCUGAUUUGACCUUGUUUUGAGGGAAUAGUCAUAAUUUCUUUGAAAGAAGUUAUUUCUCACUGAUUUUGGCUAAACAGUAUUCAUAUUUCUUCAUCUCUGUUACUGACCACUUUUCAGUAGACUGUUUCCAAAAUGUGUAUUCACAUUGACUUUCUCCCUGAUGUGAAUUCCGUGUGGGUUUUAGAUAAUAGUAAGAGAGAAGAGAUUGCUCUCCUAUAUUCAGUGAAUGAGAAGGGAACUUUUUUCUGAAGAGCAAAAUUGGUGCCCAAAAAUAUUGGACAUCUGUUUUUUGUUUUUUUUUUUUUUUUUUUUUUUUUUUGAGACGGAGUCUCGCUCUGUCACCCAGGCUGGAGUGCAGUGGCGUGAUCUUGGCUCACUGCAACCUCUGCCUCCUGGGUUCACACCAUUCUCCUGCCUCAGCCUCCCAAGUAGCUGGGACUACAGGCACCCGCAACCACACCCGGCUAAUUUUUUUUGUAUUUUUAGUAGAGAUGGGGUUUCACCAUGUUAGCCAGGAUUGUCUCCAUCUCCUGACCUCGUGAUCCACCCGCCUUGGCCUCCCAAAGAGCUGGGAUUACUGGUGUGAGCCACCGUGCCCGGCCUGGACAUCUGGUUUUAACUAGAUGGAAGGGAAGAACAUUAUGAAUCUUUAAAAUACGGCUGUUGCCAUUUUUCUCUCUUCUUAACAUGCAGCAUAGGUGACAAGCUUUUCUGUCAUCAUCAUGGAGCAUUCUGAAUCAUGACAUUUUUGUUUGAGAGUUCAUUCUUGAAUUUUCAGUUCAAAAUAUUGUUUGAACUAUUAUUCCACAUUCAAAGAUUAUAUAAGGUCCUGUGCUUUUGAAUCUUUUUCAAAACAUUUAUUUCUGCCUGCUUAAAAAAAAUACUUUUAUUUCCCCACAGAGAGUUCAGGACUUCAGAUUAGUUUGUGUUCAGCUCACUUAACUGGAUAGACAAUUUUGCGUUUUGCAACACCAUCCUGUAGGUUUUCUUUACUAGUCAAAGUGUAGGUCUUUUUAAAAUUUUUAAUCUUUAUUUUUAUUUUUAUUUUGAAACAGAGUCUCACUCUGUUGCCCAGGCUGGAGUGCAGUGGUGUGAUCUGUGCUCACUGCAACCUCUGUCACCCGGGUUUAAGCGAUUCUUCUGCCUGAGCCUCCCAAGUAGCUGGGAUUACAAGUUCCUGCCACCGUGCCUGGCUAAUUUUUGCAGUUUUAGUAGAGGCAGGGUUCCACCACCUUGGCCAGGCUGGUCUUGAACUCCUGACCUCAUGAUCCACCCACCUUGUCCUCUCAAAAUGCUUACAGGCAUGAACCACUGUGACCGGCCAGGUCUUUUUUUUUUUAAAGAGUCUAUCCUAGGCUUGGUACAGAUGGCGCCUGUGGUAAAUCUGUGUUAACAUGGUGGUAGACCAUGGAGAAUGGGUAGAUGGAGCUUCUAGACUCCAAAACAACAAAACCACAGUGUGAGUACACUGUCCCAUUAGGUUGACUGAAGUCUGAGUACAUUUUCUGGCCUGCGUGCCGUGACUUAUCCAACCUGUGAACUGAUUGUGAUCUGCUUGGUAACUUGGUUUGGUGUAAACUGCUCUUAACCCUUUGCUGAUGAAGAAAAUAAUCAUAUAAGUGGAACUA